GGUCAUUUGAAGACUCUCUCGGAAGAGAUAGCGUCUUGCUGCAACCUGCGGUCCCAGCAGAAAAACCUUGUGAUCCUUGUUGCGGGCGACAUGGAAGACGACUCACUCUAUUUGGGAGGUGACUGGCAGUUCAAUCACUUUUCAAAACUCACAUCUUCUCGGCUAGAUGCAGCUUUUGCUGAAAUCCAGCGGACUUCUCUCUCUGAAAAGUCACCACUCUCAUCUGAGACCCGUUUCGACCUCUGUGAUGAUUUGGCUCCUGUGGCAAGACAGCUUGCUCCCAGGGAGAAGCUUCCUCUGAGUAGCAGGAGACCUGCUGCGGUGGGGGCUGGGCUCCAGAAGAUAGGAAAUACCUUCUAUGUGAACGUUUCCCUGCAGUGCCUGACAUACACACUGCCGCUUUCCAACUACAUGCUGUCCCGGGAGGACUCUCAAACGUGUCAUCUUCACAAGUGCUGCAUGUUCUGUACUAUGCAAGCUCACAUCACAUGGGCCCUCCACAGUCCUGGCCAUGUCAUCCAGCCCUCACAGGUAUUGGCUGCUGGCUUCCAUAGAGGUGAGCAGGAGGAUGCCCAUGAAUUUCUCAUGUUUACUGUGGAUGCCAUGAAAAAGGCAUGCCUUCCCGGGCACAAGCAGCUAGAUCAUCACUCCAAGGACACCACCCUCAUCCACCAAAUAUUUGGAGCGUAUUGGAGAUCUCAAAUCAAGUAUCUCCACUGCCACGGCGUUUCAGACACCUUUGACCCUUACCUGGACAUCGCCCUGGAUAUCCAGGCAGCUCAGAGUGUCAAGCAAGCUUUGGAACAGUUGGUGAAGCCCAAAGAACUCAAUGGAGAGAAUGCCUAUCAUUGUGGUCUUUGUCUCCAGAAGGCGCCUGCCUCCAAGACGUUAACUUUACCCACUUCUGCCAAGGUCCUCAUUCUUGUAUUGAAGAGAUUCUCCGAUGUCACAGGCAACAAACUUGCCAAGAAUGUGCAAUAUCCUAAGUGCCGUGACAUGCAGCCAUACAUGUCUCAGCAGAACACAGGACCUCUUGUCUAUGUCCUCUAUGCUGUGCUGGUCCACGCUGGGUGGAGUUGUCACAACGGACAUUACUUCUCUUAUGUCAAAGCUCAAGAAGGCCAGUGGUAUAAAAUGGAUGAUGCCGAGGUCACUGCCUCUGGCAUCACCUCUGUCCUGAGUCAACAGGCCUAUGUCCUCUUUUACAUCCAGAAGAGUGAAUGGGAAAGACACAGUGAGAGUGUGUCAAGAGGCAGGGAACCAAGAGCCCUUGGUGCUGAAGACACAGACAGGCCAGCAACGCAAGGAGAGCUCAAGAGAGACCACCCUUGCCUCCAGGUACCCGAGUUGGACGAGCACUUGGUGGAAAGAGCCACUCAGGAAAGCACCUUAGACCACUGGAAAUUCCCCCAAGAGCAAAACAAAACGAAGCCUGAGUUCAACGUCAGAAAAGUUGAAGGUACCCUGCCUCCCAACGUACUUGUGAUUCAUCAAUCAAAAUACAAGUGUGGUAUGAAAAACCAUCAUCCUGAACAGCAAAGCUCCCUGCUAAACCUCUCUUCGACGAAACCGACAGAUCAGGAGUCCAUGAACACUGGCACACUCGCUUCUCUGCAAGGGAGCACCAGGAGAUCCAAAGGGAAUAACAAACACAGCAAGAGAUCUCUGCUUGUGUGCCAGUGA